AAAUAAACGUGGCGGGACGUAUGUGUCAUGGCGCUCUCCAUCUAAAGUCUGUGCAGCUUCCGGAGAGUGGCGGGUUGAUUUUCUCACUUUGGACUGGUUUUUACUUCCCGACUUCUGGACUCAUCUUUCAAGAGGACUUUAGACUAAUUGCAGAUAAUUAAGAGAAUAUGCCUUCUGCAUCCUGUGAUACACUACUGGAUGACAUCGAAGAUAUCGUGUCUCAGGAAGAUUCAAAACCACAAGAUAGGCAUUUUGUAAGAAAGGAUGUUGUCCCGAAGGUACGAAGGCGAAAUACCCAAAAAUAUUUGCAAGAGGAAGAAAACAGUCCACCAAGUGACAGCACUAUUCCAGGCAUACAGAAAAUUUGGAUACGAACAUGGGGUUGUUCUCAUAAUAAUUCAGAUGGAGAAUAUAUGGCUGGACAGCUAGCUGCUUAUGGCUAUAAAAUUACAGAAAAUGCAUCCGAUGCAGAUUUAUGGCUCCUGAACAGUUGCACUGUAAAAAACCCAGCUGAAGACCACUUUAGAAACUCAAUUAAAAAAGCUCAAGAGGAGAACAAGAAAAUCGUACUGGCUGGAUGCGUUCCUCAAGCCCAGCCUCGCCAGGACUACCUUAAGGGACUGAGUAUCAUUGGGGUUCAGCAGAUAGAUCGUGUGGUAGAAGUUGUGGAGGAGACAAUUAAAGGUCACUCUGUGAGACUGCUGGGUCAGAAAAAGGAUAAUGGAAGGCGGCUUGGGGGAGCACGAUUGGAUUUGCCGAAGAUUAGGAAGAAUCCACUGAUAGAAAUCAUUUCCAUCAAUACCGGGUGUCUCAAUGCUUGUACCUACUGCAAAACUAAACACGCCAGAGGAAAUUUGGCCAGUUAUCCAAUUGAUGAACUAGUAGAUAGAGCCAAACAAUCUUUUCAAGAGGGUGUUUGUGAGAUAUGGUUGACCAGUGAAGACACGGGGGCUUAUGGCAGAGAUAUUGGCACCAAUCUCCCCACACUCCUGUGGAAACUGGUUGAAGUGAUUCCUGAGGGAGCAAUGCUGAGGCUUGGCAUGACAAAUCCGCCCUAUAUUUUAGAGCAUCUGGAGGAAAUGGCAAAAAUCCUUAAUCACCCCAGAGUCUACGCUUUUCUGCACAUACCAGUCCAGUCUGCCUCCGACAGCGUACUCAUGGAAAUGAAAAGAGAAUACUGUGUGGCUGACUUCAAAAGAGUAGUGGAUUUUCUGAAAGAGAAAGUUCCUGGAAUAACUAUUGCUACAGAUAUUAUCUGUGGUUUUCCUGGAGAAACAGAUCAGGAUUUUCAAGAAACAGUGAAACUUGUUGAAGAGUACAAAUUCCCAAGCCUGUUUAUUAACCAAUUUUACCCAAGACCAGGAACUCCUGCUGCAAAAAUGGAACAAGUUCCAGCACAAGUGAAAAAGCAAAGGACAAAAGAUCUUUCUCGGGUGUUUCAUUCUUACAGUCCAUAUGAUCACAAGAUUACCUAAACACAGAUCCCUAUCAUUCAGCCACUCCAGCCAUGUACUACGCAGAUCCAAGGAAGGAGUACCAAACACAUCUCAGUUUAGGCGGCCUUGCGCAUCAGUGUUCAAGAAAUAUUUCCAUUCGACUCUUAGAGUACCAGCAAUUUUUGAAACACUGUUCCAUUUUCUAAAUUUUUUUGAGUCUUUUAUCUCUCCUAUUCUAUUUAAUCACCCUACUAUAUAAAGCCAUUUGAAUAAUUCAUGUUCACUGGUUCAGAAGUAGGUGAUGUUUUGAAAAUUCAUUUUUAUAUGAAUUAGAUAUAUAUGAUUUAGUAAUUUGUAUAUGUCCCCAAUUAUAUUCUUAACCUGUUUUUUCUAAUAGUGUUUUGACAUGACUUUUUAACACUUGUCAUCUAUAUUGACAACCUCAUUGGCAGGGUAGAGGUAUGUGAUUUCUUUUUUUUUUUUUUUUUUUUUUUAAUCGUUAAGCGUUUAACCAUGAACUCUCAAAUACAAAGAAAAGAAUUGCCUCUGUGUGGAUUUAUUUAAGACUGUAAUGAAUUAACCUAAUGCCAUUUGAAUUUAGAUUGCUUCUGCCUCUAUUCUGAUAAGUUAGCGAACAUAUGUGACAUUCAUUCAAUUAUGGCAGCUGUUUAAUCAUCAAUAGUAAUAUUUUAUCUUAAUCAUAAUGUAGGCUGUAUCACCUCUAGAUUUGUGUGCCCAUAUGAGAAGACGGGUAUCAUUCUCUUAGCUAGCAACAGGAUUCCUCUUAGGAAAGGAGCUGGCUUUGCUUAGGAAACUAUCUUGAUAAACAGUUCAAUGGACAAAGUUAAAACCUGAGGACAUGAGUUACAAGGAAACAAGACUAGGAAAGACAGAACUAACUGCUCAGCAGUAGAAAAAAAAUAGAGGGAUUUUUUUCUCUUAGCAUAAAUGAGAGAAAGGGUAAUAAAAGAGAGGGAAGAAGUGGGGAAUAACUAAUAUUCAGUUUUAAGUGGUUUGCAUUUUUCCCUGUGUGGACAGAACUAAGCCAGAAAACAAAAAAUUGAGAGCUAGAUAAGACCUGGAGAAUGCAGGUCCUCUGGAUGUUUAAAGUCAUUUGAGAAGGACACUGGACUUUUUUCACACAGGGCAAGGAUGGGGAAAUUAGAGCCAAUCUAACUAGAUCCAAAGGGGCGGGGAGACUCCAGAUGACAUCUGGGUCUCAUAGAUAUUCAUGCCUGCCUUUAAUUCCCAGCCCUGCCUUUUACUAGCUGUGUACCUUUGGGAAAGAUACUUAAUUGCCCUGUGUCUCGGUUUCCUCAUCCAUAACAUGGGAAUCUCAAAAGUGCAUUUUAAACAGGUUGUCAUGGUGAUUAAAUUAAUGCAUGUGGAAGAGGUUGGGAAAAUGUUUUGCGUGUAAGUACUGGUUAAAUGCCACACACAUCAUCCAUACUCAUGGAAACACACAUAUGAUAGAAGAUUUGGGUUUGCUUUUUAUGUGCAUGCUUUAAACUUAACUGCAAAGAAGUAAUACAUCAAAAACCCAUUCUAAGGAAACAAAGUUGGCCCAGUACCCCUAAUUUCUAGCAACUUCAUCUCUCCCUUAAAUGGAAAAUAUUUUAUACCCUAAACAAAUUAACUAAUGAGUAACUUACUUUCUAUAAAACAAUGUUUAACUCCAUAUGUCAUCAUGUAUUUUCAAAGACCAAAAUUUUAUCAAUAUCUGGAUAUAUUAACCAAUCCUUAUACUUUUGCUCCUUGAGAAAAAUGUAUUGCUUAGUUUCUGAAGCAAUGGUGUAACUAGGUCUUUUGAUAUAAUGUUAAAUGUUUUAAUCAUUUGACUCUUGUCUACAUGAAAUGGAAAUGUAAAUUGCUUUCUAAAAGUUGUUAAGCUUCAGUGGUGGCUAAAUACUCUACAAUGUGUAAAAUAUUAAAAUACCAGAGUAGGCUGGGCACAGUGGCUCACACCUGUAAUCCCAGCACUUUGGGAGUCCAAGGCAGGCAGAUCACGAAGUCAAGAGAUGGAGACCAUCCUGGCCAACAUGAUGAAACCCUGCCUCUACUAAAAAUACCAAAAAAAAAUUAGCUGGGUGUGGUGGCACACACCUGUAAUGCCAGCUACUCAGGAGGCUGAGGCAGGGGAAUCACUUGAACCCAGGAGGCGGAGGUUUCAGUGAGCCGAUUGUGCCACUGCACUCCAGCCUGGCCACAGAGCGAGACUCCGUCCCCCACCCCCCCCAAAAAAAAAAAAUACAAGAGUGAUGACAUUAAGAAUGUAAUUGCUGUCUAUUUUGAUUGCUUUUAUUUAAAACGUUUACUGCUGACCUAUUGGUAGCCAUUUAGAAUAUUUACCACAUUUAUUACAAUAUAUCUAGAAACUCAGUUGUAAAAAAUUUUAUAAUUCGAUUCCUCAAAAUCCUUUAGAAAACAUUUAGAUUUAGAUUUUAAAAUGUUUAGAACAUAUUUUUCCCUAAGCAAUUGUUUUAUCUAGUUUUUUUUCCCCCCGAAUUAUAUUAUGUGUCAUCAGCGUGUGUGAGGAUGGGGAGGACAGCUUUAAGAAGCUGCUGCAUUUAGUACCAAUUCCUUGUACAAUUGGGAGGAGACUUUUGAAAUAAAAUAUUCUGUUUCCCCAGCUCAAGCUGGACAUGAAAAUCAGAAACAUGGAAGGAGAAGGGGCAUAGCCGUGACAGGAAGGGGAAGGAAUUUGAUUUGAGGAGCGCCUGGAGAAGCCUAGUCUCACCCAGGACAUCACCUCCCAUGGUAGCACCUUUGCUAUCACUUAGUACAUUUUCUGUCUUGAGACGGUGAAAGCUCUUUAAGAGCAGGCACCGUGUCUCCUUGCUGUAUUUCAGUGCCUAGCACGUAUAGAAGGUUAAUGAGUAUUUGUUGAAUGAAUUAGUUGAUUCACUUAUAAGUCACUUUGCAAUUUGGUGAUUAUUCAUUAUGUUCAAGAGACCUGUUUCCCAUGCAUUAGUAAUUAGUCCUACUGGGAAUGAAAUUUCAUAAAAUCUGUGAGAAGGGCAGCCUGACAGUGUGUGUCCAGGCCUUCCAAAUGUGCUCCAGAAUAUAUUAUAAAGGGACAGGGACGGAUCUGAGUAAACAUAAAUCUGUGAAGAUGUUCAUUGCAGAACUGUUUAUAGUAAUAAAAUGUAAAGAACAACCUAAAUAUCCCAUAGUGGGUGAUGAGUUAAAUAAAUGUUGCAUUCAUAUGGCAUAAUGGUAGUGACUAAAAUCAUGUUAUAGGAGAAUAUUUAGUGAUAGGGAGGGGAGCGUUCACUGAUAUUUCAAAAACUGAAAAUGUAUUACGAGAUAACAUGUAUGUGAUCCUAAUUUCAUAAAAAUUAUUAUUACACAUUUGCUUAGGAAAAAUAAGACUGAGCGGGGCAUGGUGGCUCACACCUGUAAUCCUAGCACUUUGGGAAGCUGAGGCAGGUGGAUCACUUGAGCUCAGGAGUUUGAGACCAGCCUGGGCAACAUGGUGAAACUCUGUCUCUAUAAAAAAUUUUUAAAAAAUUAGCUGGGCAUGGUAGCUUGUGCCUGUAGUCCCAGCUACUGGCAGGGCUGAGGUGGGAGGAUAGCUUGAGCCCAGGAGGCAGAAGUUGCAGUGAGCCGAGAUCGUGCCACUGUACUCCAGCUUGGGUGACAGAGCGAGACCCUGUCUCCAAAAAAAAAAAAAAAAAAGGAAAAAUAAGACUGGUAAAAUAUACACUACAGUGUUAACACUAGUUAUCUUUAGCAGAAUCCCUUUUUUUCCUUUUUGUGCUUUUUCUAUAUUUUUGAAAAUUUCUAAAAUGAACAUUUAUUCCUUUUGUAAAGAAGGGAAAGAGAAAGGAAAGUUUUCCAGUGCCAUUUUGUGGAGUGAUGGGACAAAUUUGUCUGAAAGGAAUUGAAACGGGAAUGGGAGGUUUAGAAGGAAGAACGAUGGAUGUAAGGAAGAUAGUGAGACAUGGAUCAACUCUGAGCUGCAGCCACUGGAGAAUUUGUGUGGUGGGAUUACUAGAAUUCAAGCAGCUGGAGAGGUGCAGAGAGAUCCCUAGGAGCAAGACUGGUGUGCAUGCUGCUGUGGUUGCUUUGGCAUGGAAUCCUUCUAAGAGUAUCAAACUGUAUAAAGUAGGUAGGAAACAGAACCUUGUAUGCCUGGUAAACUUUGCCAAGGAGAAGGGUCUGCUCUCUGCCUAGGCUGGUUUUUCAGCAUAUGAUUUAAGCAUAUUUUCCUUUGACUCUUCAUAUGUGUUUAUUGAUUUCUUUUUCUGCGCCAUAUUCUUUGUUUCUACUGUGAUGCUUAGAGAGAUGGUAGGUAGGGUGGAAAGAGAUACGCUUUGAACUUGGCAGAAUUCAGCCGACAUAGAUUUGAUCCCUGCUCUAUCACUUAUGAGCUCUAUGACCUUGGAAAAAUUUGCUCCAGUGCUCCUAGCCAGCAGUGUUAGAAUGAUGCUGAUAAUAAUCACCUUGCAAGGUUUUAAGCAAGAUACAUUUAUGUAAAGUCACCAACUCAGUUCCUUUCACGAUAAUGGGCAGCCAGUAAAUGUUACUUAUUGUUCUCAAGAUUGUCUUUUCUCAGCCAGACACUGUUGUAUAUAUGCCUGUAAUCCCAGCUACUCAGGAGGUUGAAGUGGGAGGAUAGCCUGGAGUUUGAGACCAGCCUGGGCAACAUAGUGAGAUCCUGUCUCAAAGAAACAAACAAAAAACGAAAGAUUGUCUUUUCUCAUUGUUCUUUCUUGAUUACACAAACACAGUGUGUCUUAUAAUUACAAAGCCAUAUGCUUGUGUUGAUAUCUUGUUUAUUUGUUUUUGUAGUUUUUACUUAAGUAAUAUAAAAAAAUAGCUAAGUGAAAAUCUUCACGAAUGAAAGCAACCUCUUUGUUUGUUCCUCGUCAUCCUAACCAAAAUCAGUAGUUUGAUAGUACUUCUGUUUCAUUAUGACAUACAUCUACCAGUCACCUAACCUGGCCUUACUGAAACAAAACAGUCUUUGAGAAAUGUAAGCACAUCACUCAGCCUUGUUAUGGAAAACUGGCAGAGCACCUGGGUGUGCCCAGAGGGACUGUGAUUUCACUUCUCACUCCAUAAGCAACAUCCUUCUGUUGUGAAUUAAAUCUUCACAGUCAAAAUCUGUGUCUGCAUGUGCUUGUUUAUUUGGAAAAGAAAUGUUAUUCAGAGAGGCAUUUUAUUUGUAAUACUUGUGGAGCAAUAUGAUAUUAAGUGAGCUUAAUAUUGGUAGAGUGCUCUUUUCAUUUUAAAGAUUCUUCACAUGCAUUUGUUUUUCUUUCUGGCUUUCCUCUCUGUUAUUAGGCCAACAGACAAGUUAUAUUUUAUACAUAUGUGUCAGUAUGAUGCUUUACAUGUGUUUAUAACAUAUAUGAAUAUGGUAUAUACUCUUCUGUUUGUGAAUUGCUGUGCAUAUCUGAGGAUACGCAUGUUAGUGAACUGGUUUCAAUUUACACAAGGAGGUUUCUUUUUUCUGCUUUCAUCCAACCUUUAUUGAGGACAGUAAAUACUGCCUCUUAUCUCCCAUCCCAAGCUGAGUUCAGCAUCUGGAGAAGCUUAAGGUCCCAAUGCAUCAAAUUAUCUUGCUCAAACUGUUGUUUAUUACAGUCAAUUUUGUCCUGUCACUCCAGUGGCAGAAUGUCAAAGCUUUUCUUUGCAUUGCCUUCAGCUUUUAGCCUCUGCAGGGAUCUGAUAUGCUGCUCCUGCUUUGCCAGGGGGUGGGUUGGAGGGGACUCAAAGGGUCAUGAUGAAGCUCCAAGCCAGAUAACUACAGCACUGGUUAACCUCCUUGCUAAAGCUGGGAAGGGUUUAUGCCCCACCAUUUCACUCCCUGGACCACAAACAUGCACUUCAUUUUAUGAAUGUCUGUUAAUUUCCUAUGUUUCCAUUUCUUUUCUUUUGAGACCUGUGUAACCACAAGCAAAGCAUGUAUGAUGGUAUUCAUAGAAGAAUAGACAGUGUAAGUCUAGAAACUUAAUGUGAAUUUUGUCACUGACAAAUAUGUAUUCUGUAAUCUGAACAGUUUAAUUUAGAUAAAUAGUUUAUCUUUUAAAACUCUGACUAGAAUAAACAUUCACAUGAAUUUCCCAUUUAAGUGUUUAAAACUUCAACUUCUAACCUUUUUUUCAGUUAGAAACAUAUAUGUACCUAAUUAUUUCUUUUUAGUUUUAUAUAAUUGUGAUCAUGUGUAUAAUUAUACAUGAUGUAGCUUUCUGGGAUGAAGUUUUGUUGUGACAAAAGGUGCUUUCCAAAUACGUUUUUGUUUUGACCAUUGUCAACAUAGUUAAUAAUCUGUAGAAGUUUGCCUAAUGCCUUCCUCUGGGGCUUCUUGACCUUGUUUUCUGAAACCUCCUUUUUUUUUUUUUUUUAAUUUUUUUAAUGACUCCUGUAAUGUCUCAUCAAAAAAAGCAGUUUCUAUAGUAUUCUUGAAAAAUGAGUGUAAUAGAGUUGGGGAUGAUAAAUAUAUUUCCAGGAUGGAAUACAACUUAUUCAGAUAAGAAAAAAUCUGGCAAUAAUGAAACAUUUCACACUGAUUAUAAGCUAGGAAAUAUUCCUGUGUUUCUACUUAAAAUCAGCUUUAGCCCAAGCAACCUCUUCUUUUGCUUGGACUAUGGAAGUUGCCUUCUGACUGGUCCCUCCAUACCCAUUCUUGUUCCUCUCUCGAAUCUGUUCUUCCAAGGGAAACUAGAAUGAUCUUUUAUACAAGCUGUCAUAGCAACCUGUGACACUACUCUUCAUAUACAUCACACUUGCCAUUUUAUAUGUGUGUGAUUAUUUGAUCACUGUCCAUCUCCCUUACUAGAUUGUAAGUUCCAGAAGGGCAGAGGCCAUGCCUGGCCUAUGGUAGAUGCUCAGUGAAGAGUUAUGGGACACUUAAAUGAAGACAGUCAGAUCUGUACUAAGUUUUGUGUUGUGAAAGUAUGUCCUCAGUUGUCCUGGUUUACACGGUUCUCACAGAUAAUCCACUCUGAACAGCGACACCUAAUUCACUUAACCACCACUUGGUUGAGAUCUUACCUCCUGUUCUGAGUCCGCACCAUAGGCUAGCCUUUUAAAAAUUAAACCCUUACUUCAGGCAGAGUUUGAGAUUCAAAAAUUUCUCCAUAGUUCCACCCAACCCAGAUUGGGUUUGAGAAUAUGCUUAUGUAACAGACAAGAGUGGGAGAUUAUUGACUUCCUAGCUGCUCUUGAAAAAGAUCUUUGCAAUGAGGCCUGAUUAUUUUCAUAUCAUGUAUUUCCAGAACAAGCAAUGUGCAAAAACCCUCUGUGACACCAAAUGUAUAGGAUUUGUUCUUGUGAUUUUGGGCUACUUUUUGCAUGUCUCAGUUUUCAACAGUUCUCUGAGGAAGCACUUUGCUUAUUUGGCAAAAUAAGCAUAUUCGUGGUCCACAUUGCAGACCCGCUUUAAGUCACCUAUCUCCAGGUUUGAAAGUUUCCGUGGAAGAAUCAAUAAGUCGCUUUUGGCUCUAAAAUGGCUCCUGAGCAGUCACCUUUUUGUUUUCAUCCCAUCUGUUGUUUUCGAAUGGGAAAUAAAGAUUUUCUUUUUUUUCUUUUUUUCUUUUUUUUGAGAUGAAGUCUCGCUCUGUCACCCAGGCUGGAGUACAGUGGCGCAAUCUCGGCUCACUGCAACCUCUGCCUCCCGGGUUCAAGUGAUUCUUCUGCUUCAGCCUCCUGAGUAGCUGGGAUUACAGGCGCCCACCACCAUGCCCAGCUAAUUUUUGCAUUUUUAGUAGAGACGGGGUUUCACCGUGUUGGUCAGGCUGGUCUCGAACUUCUGACUUCGUGAUCUACCCUCCUUGGCCUCCCAAAGUGCUGGGAUUACAGGCGUGAGCCACCGCACCCAGCCAAGAUUUUUUUUUUUUUAUUCACUGUAAUUUUUGGACACAGACACACACACACACACACACGUGUGUGUGUGUGUGUGUGUGUCUGUGUCCAAAAAUAUAUAUAUAUGUAUAUAUAUUUUUUAACUUUAAUUUCUGGUAUACGUGUGCAGAACAUACAGGUUUGUUACAUAGGUAUACAUGUGCCAUGGUGGUUUGCUGCACCUGUCAACCCGUCAUCUAGGUUUUUAGCCCUGCGUGCAGGUAUUUGUCCUAAUGCUCUCCCUCCCCUUGCCCCCCACUCUCCGAUGGGCUCUGGUGUGUGAUGUUCCCCUCCCUGUGGACACAUACAUAUUUUCAUUUAAACAGUGGCUAAUCCAGUCAAGAGAAUAGAUCCUGGAAGAUUAGAAAAUGCAAAUUAAGAAAAAAAAUAGGGAUCAAUGGUAAUACAGGAAGCCCCUUUUGUUGGCUGGGGGGGUGCAGUGAAGGUAGUGUCAAGGAACAGGGAAGACAACCACCCUGUUGCUGGUGACACCCAGCCUGACCUUUGGUGUCAGCUCAUAGUAAUCACUUUGCUGUCCUGAGUUAAAAGCUAUCAUGAAAACCUUAUGUUGAAUGGGCCCAUCUUCCUUAUGUACUUGACAAGGCUACAUUUUUUCCCUCCCCUCCAACGAUAUCGUAUGAGAUUGACGUUAUCAGAAUAAAAAUACUAUGGAUUGCUGUAUUUUUCAAUACAGCACCAGAUCAGUAAACACCAUCUUAUAAGUAACAAUGACUUUCUGCUUCAUUAAAAAAUUAUUUAUGCUAUAGAAAAACAAUAUUGAAUGGUAGUUCCUUUGUAGAAACUACAGCUGGUGCAUGCUGUAGCUCUCUUUUCAGUCAGUGUAAGAGAUAAACUGUUAGCAAUAAUAGAGAGAUGCCCAUUGAACUGAAUAUGCUCUUUUUAAGAUAAAGAACUUUUUGGUGGUGUUAAUCACUUAUUUGCCUUUCUAGAGAAUGUAUCCACUUAAUAUAUUUAUAGGGGUGAUCUACGUUUCAGAUUUAUAAAGUCUCUGAAUAUAUAUUUUUAACUAUACACAUAAAAAUUAAAUUUAGAGAAAAGAGUCUCAAAAUUCACUCUUCUGUAAAGCUAACAUAUAAACUCUGCUUCUGCAUGGCUUCUUUUAUGGGCUUGGAGUAAUUAAGCAGACAUAAUAUAACACAUAAAGGAAUUUAUUAGGCUUUUAUUAAGGCUUGAUAAUUUGAGUUUCAGAUUUUAAAUCUCAAAGGGCUCAUAAUUGUUGUCAUUUUCUACUAAAAGCUGCAUUUAGAAAGAAGUUAAACUGUGGUGCAAAGGAAAGGCACGUUUCAAUGGAAAAUUCAAAAUGCCUUUUUCAUUAAUUCAGCACUUGAAUGCAAGUGCCUAUUGUGCCUAGCGGGAGGCUUUUAAUAAGUAAUACAGACGCUGCUUACAUGACUUAAUUUAUGCCGAUAUUUUCUUGAAACUGUGUUAGUUGCAGGAAGUAGAGGUUUGAGGUUGAGAUAUGUCCUGGUAGAGAGGGAAGAGAUUAUUUCAAACUCCAGAAAUGUGAGUGAAUUCUAAUUUGCCAAGCCAAUUUAAGUCUUAGAAGUAAGGUUUUUAAUUUCACUAUUGACUCAAGAAAUCACUGGGACCAUUCCAGGUCUCUGCAGGAUGAAUUUUGGAAUAGUUUGUAACAUUGAACAGCCAUCUUCUGAUUAAACAUCUUCUCUCCUUGUUAACUCCUAAUUCCCCAUAAAAUAAUCUAUUUGGGGUCAUGGAAAUGUUCCCCAACAAAAGCAAUACUUUAAAAUUUAAGAAACCUAGAACUGAAAGCUGAACCUCUGAUGGAAAACAGGUAAAUGGGGCAUUGAACUCUGAGGCCCAUUCCAUGGUUUUGCCCAGAACCAGCUCUGGCCUUGAGAUUUGAGUUAGCAGAAUUCCAGUUAACUGAAACUUUGCUCUAGAAUUGAAAGUAAAAACAAAAGCCACCUGACUCAAUCAGUCUCAGCAUCACAUAUGUAACUUCCUUGAUGCUUGUUAGCUUUGAAGGACCUAGAAAAAGUCUGGCCUGCUGGGCACAGUAGCUGACGCCUGUAAUCCUAGCUACUCAGGAGGCUGAGGUGGGAGAAUCGCUGGAGCCCAGGGGUUUGAGACCAGCCUGGGCAACAUAGCAAGACCUUGUCUCUAAAAAAAAGGUUUUCUUAAUUAGUUGGGUGUGGUGGCAUGUGUCUGUAGUCCCAGCUGCUCAGGAGGCUGAGGUGGGAGGAUCACUUGAGCCCAGGAGUUUGAGGCUGUAGUGUGCAAUGAUCACACCUAUGUAUAGCCACUGCACUCCAGCCUGGGCAACACAGCAAGAACUCAUCUUGAUGGAAGAAAGAAAGGAAGGAAAGGACAAGAGGGAAAGGGGGAGGGAGGAAGAGAGAGAGGGCCUGGCUUGAAUAGCUUAACUAAUGCCACAGCUGAACCCUUCUAUGGUAAUCACAGUGAGGCCAACUGGGACAGAACAAUAUUAGGAAUCAACUCCCUAGCACACAAAAUCUGCCUUUAAAUUUAAGCCUGAUGUAUAACGCUAGCAAAUGCCCGUUUUGCCUCCUCCUCACUGCCAGCACAACCUUGCCUUGUGCAAAAGUCACUUCUCUUGAGAUUACUGCAGAUGUGGUGGUUGUUCCUGAGUUCUCGUUCAUGAGCCACCUUCCUGGGGUCGGUUUUAUAACCUCCUCCACUUCAUUCUCUCAGUGAUGCAGAGGCCUCACAUACAUCAUUAGCUGCUUUAGACUGGAUCCUGACCUCUUAAUCUUCACAGUAACCCAAAACAAACACCCGCUUGGGGCCACCGGCAGAACCCACCGUGGUUUGGGAAUACAGUAGCCUUUAGUGUCUUGAUUUCAAGUCACCAUCUUUUUCACUUUCCUCAUCUGUUUCUUUUUCAUCCUAGUCAUGUUCCCUCUCCCUCAAAAGUUCUUUAACCAAUCAUCCAAAAUCCUUACUGUGGAGGCCUCUAAACCACAGGCGUUUGUCAGAUGAAAAUCAGAAAAAGGCAUGUGGUGUUGAGUCAUAAUCUUAAACUUUGUAGUCUUGAAAUAAUGCUGUUAUCUGGCCGGGCGCGGUGGCUCAUGCCUGUAAUCCCAGCACUUCAGGAGGCCGAGAGACGGGUGGAUCACCUGAGGUCAGGAGUUUGAGACCAGCCUGGCCAACAUGGCAAACCCCAUCUCUACUAAAAAUACCAAAAUCAGCCAGGCAUGGUGGUGCAUCCUGUAAUCUCAGCUACUUGGAAGGCUGAGGCAGGAGAAUCCCUUGAACCUGGGAGACGGAGGCUGCAGUAAGCCAACAUCACACCAUUACACUCCAGCCUGGGCAAGAGGAGCGAAACUCUAUCUCAAAAACAAAAAAAGAAAAGAAAAAGAAAUAAUGUGUCUAUUUUAGUUAUUAAUUAGGCUCCCUGUCCCUAGCAUUGCCCCUCUACCUAGCUCCAGAAUGACCUAUUCCACUGCUCCUAAUUGUUGGUCUACUAAAUGCUGGUCCAGGAUGACAUUUUCACCAAACUGCAGAAGAGAUAAGAAAAACAAAGACAGUACAACUUACAGCUUAAAUUGAUGAUUUAAAAGAUUUAAAAUCACUUCCUAUUUUGAAAUGAUUUAUUGUGAUCAUAGAUUUGAAAUUUUAAAAAAUUAUGUACCUGCUUGUAGAAUGAAAAGUACACAACCUUAUAAACAAGCUGGGUUUUUUAAAAAAUUUCCACUCAUUUUACUAGCAUUUAGAAUCUCAAAAACUGGGACCUAGAUUUAGCCAGAACCCAGAAAACUGGGACCUAGGAUCUAGCCAGAACCCAGAUUUAACCUCACUGCCAUGCCUCAUACCCUAUAGCAGCCACUGUAACCUACAAAAGCAAGUCCAGGUGCUUCAACCAUAACACACACAGACCGGGGCUGGCCCUUUACCACUAUCCAUCAUUGUCUCCCAGCAUUCCCUGUCCUGGAACUAAAUUGGCUUGAUGCCAUUUAUGCCUAAUAUUGCUAGCCAGGUAAAAUCCAUCCAUGAUGGUCAAGUGUAAACUUAGAAGCUUAUAUUCAUAAACACAGACUCAAAAAUUCUCAGCAUCAAAGAUGAGGUCAGAAUGCCCCCUCAUCUUCCCUGACUACUUUCUGCUUGAAACAGGCUUCCCGCCUUUAUAAACUGGAUUCACUGUAUUCAUCAUCCUUGAAGCUUGACUUGACCAGCUUUGUGCCAGCCUUUAAGCCACCACUGUAGCUUGCCUCUUCAUCAACAGCAUGUAUACAUAAUAUUGGAAAGAAUCUUUUUAAAAAAAUGUCUUUGCCAUCACUAGGCUGUAAAGCUCCACCAGAGGAAUCUAAUUCAUCUUCAUGGCAUAGCACACACUGGGAAGAUUUCUCUUUAAACUGAAAUGAACGAAUAGACAGCUAAGAUGUGGUUAAUCAAUGUGAAAGCAAAAACCCUUUCUUUCCUCCUUCCCCAGGUGUCUCUUCAAAGGAAUAAACUUCCUUCCUGGCCAAAGCCUUGUGGCAAAGUAAUUGACCACAGCUUUGACAGCAACAAAGAUGACCUCUUCACAUCCACUUCCUUAGCCCUUUCCUUCCACUUUCUGUUUCAGGAGAAGAAGGACCAUUUUGUUGUUAUUAAAAUGACUAUGCUGUUCUAAGAA